GUCCAGGGAGGUGAUGUUUGAGUUGGGUCUUGAAGGAUGGGUAGGAGUUUGCCAGCCAGGCAAAGCUAGUAGUAGCAGAGCCAAAAUUUAAACCUGAACAGUCUGGCUCCAGACUCUGUGUUCUUUCCUGCAGCAUGCUUGGCCCUGCUGCCCUACAAGGCCUAGCCUUGGGAGGUGAGACUCUGGGUCCUGGGUCACUCCACGUGAGCCCUAGACCAUUUUCCCAUCCAAUUCCUGCUUUUGCUCUUCACAAACUCCCACUCUCUCCCCCUUCUGCAAAGGUGGUUGGGAGUUGACUAGCCUUGUAGGCAGUCUGUGUCUCUCUAAGUGACUAGGAUUUGUGGUGUGCUGAGAAGGGUACACAGAUUCUACCCUCAGUUCUCCUGUGGCAGGUAGGAGGCACAGACAGACAGAGAAGCAUUUCCUGGUUUGUUUUUCCACUGUUUGCCCCGAGCACAUGAACUGUGCUUUGCAUAAGGCACCUCCUCAGAUCAUUGCAACAACCCUGGCAGGUAGAGGUAAUUUACUGCCGUUUUAAGCAUGAGAAAGGUGACUCACAGAGGUUGAGCCAUGUGUCCAAGGUCACACAGCUAAGCCAGUAAGUAGAGGGACUGGAAUUUGCACCUCAAUCUAACUGCAAGGCCUGUACUCGUGUUUUUAAGCCAUCAGGAAGAAUACCAGGUUAUGAAGGCCACGCCCCUUUCUGGUGAGUCUCACCUCUGUGCUGGUAAUCAGGACACCCAGGAAUUGCAAGUCGGCGGUAGCAAGCAUAAGGUUGCAUUGAUUUCAGUGCUUCUCAACGGACAUGUGCAUGAGAAUCAUCAGGAAUGCUGGUUACAAAUGCAAGUUUCAUUGCCCUCAUCCUAGAGGUUCUAACUCAAUGUCGACGUACAAGCGGGCCACGCUGGACGAGGAGGACCUGGUGGACUCGCUCUCCGAGGGCGACGCAUACCCCAACGGCCUGCAGGUGAACUUCCACAGCCCCCGGAGUGGCCAGAGGUGCUGGGCUGCACGGACCCAGGUGGAGAAGCGGCUGGUGGUGUUGGUGGUACUUCUGGCGGCAGGACUGGUGGCCUGCUUGGCAGCACUGGGCAUCCAGUACCAGACAAGAUCCCCCUCUGUGUGCCUGAGCGAAGCUUGUGUCUCAGUGACCAGCUCCAUCUUGAGCUCCAUGGACCCCACAGUGGACCCCUGCCAUGACUUCUUCAGCUACGCCUGUGGGGGCUGGAUCAAGGCCAACCCAGUCCCUGAUGGCCACUCACGCUGGGGGACCUUCAGCAACCUCUGGGAACACAACCAAGCAAUCAUCAAGCACCUCCUCGAAAACUCCACGGCCAGCGUGAGCGAGGCAGAGAGAAAGGCGCAAGUAUACUACCGUGCGUGCAUGAACGAGACCAGGAUCGAGGAGCUCAGGGCCAAACCUCUAAUGGAGUUGAUUGAGAGGCUCGGGGGCUGGAACAUCACAGGUCCCUGGGCCAAGGACAACUUCCAGGACACCCUGCAGGUGGUCACCGCCCACUACCGCACCUCACCCUUCUUCUCUGUCUAUGUCAGUGCCGAUUCCAAGAACUCCAACAGCAACGUGAUCCAGGUGGACCAGUCUGGCCUGGGCUUGCCCUCGAGAGACUAUUACCUGAACAAAACUGAAAACGAGAAGGUGCUGACCGGAUAUCUGAACUACAUGGUCCAGCUGGGGAAGCUGCUGGGCGGCGGGGACGAGGAGGCCAUCCGGCCCCAGAUGCAGCAGAUCUUGGACUUUGAGACGGCACUGGCCAACAUCACCAUCCCACAGGAGAAGCGCCGUGAUGAGGAGCUCAUCUACCACAAAGUGACGGCAGCCGAGCUGCAGACCUUGGCACCCGCCAUCAACUGGUUGCCUUUUCUCAACACCAUCUUCUACCCCGUGGAGAUCAAUGAAUCCGAGCCUAUUGUGGUCUAUGACAAGGAAUACCUUGAGCAGAUCUCCACUCUCAUCAACACCACCGACAGAUGCCUGCUCAACAACUACAUGAUCUGGAACCUGGUGCGGAAAACAAGCUCCUUCCUUGACCAGCGCUUUCAGGACGCCGAUGAGAAGUUCAUGGAAGUCAUGUACGGGACCAAGAAGACCUGUCUUCCUCGCUGGAAGUUUUGCGUGAGUGACACAGAAAACAACCUGGGCUUUGCGUUGGGCCCCAUGUUUGUCAAAGCAACCUUCGCCGAGGACAGCAAGAGCAUAGCCACCGAGAUCAUCCUGGAGAUUAAGAAGGCAUUUGAGGAAAGCCUGAGCACCCUGAAGUGGAUGGAUGAGGAAACCCGAAAAUCAGCCAAGGAAAAGGCCGAUGCCAUCUACAACAUGAUAGGAUACCCCAACUUCAUCAUGGAUCCCAAGGAGCUGGACAAAGUGUUUAAUGACUACACUGCAGUUCCAGACCUCUACUUUGAAAAUGCCAUGCGGUUUUUCAACUUCUCAUGGAGGGUCACUGCCGAUCAGCUCAGGAAAGCCCCCAACAGAGAUCAGUGGAGCAUGACCCCGCCCAUGGUGAACGCCUACUACUCGCCCACCAAGAAUGAGAUUGUGUUUCCGGCCGGGAUCCUGCAGGCACCAUUCUACACACGCUCCUCACCCAAGGCCUUAAACUUUGGUGGCAUAGGUGUCGUCGUGGGCCAUGAGCUGACUCAUGCUUUUGAUGAUCAAGGACGGGAGUAUGACAAGGACGGGAACCUCCGGCCAUGGUGGAAGAACUCAUCCGUGGAGGCCUUCAAGCGUCAGACCGAGUGCAUGGUAGAGCAGUACAGCAACUACAGCGUGAACGGGGAGCCGGUGAACGGGCGGCACACCCUGGGGGAGAACAUCGCCGACAACGGGGGUCUCAAGGCGGCCUAUCGGGCUUACCAGAACUGGGUGAAGAAGAACGGGGCUGAGCACUCGCUCCCCACCCUGGGCCUCACCAAUAACCAGCUCUUCUUCCUGGGCUUUGCACAGGUCUGGUGCUCCGUCCGCACACCUGAGAGCUCCCACGAAGGCCUCAUCACCGAUCCCCACAGCCCCUCUCGCUUCCGGGUCAUCGGCUCCCUCUCCAAUUCCAAGGAGUUCUCAGAACACUUCCGCUGCCCACCUGGCUCACCCAUGAACCCGCCUCACAAGUGCGAAGUCUGGUAAGGACGAAGCGGAGAGAGCCAAGACGGAGGAGGGGAAGGGGCUGAGGACGAGACCCCCAUCCAGCCUCCAGGGCAUUGCUCAGCCCGCUUGGCCACCCGGGGCCCUGCUUCCUCACACUGGCGGGUUUUCAGCCGGAACCGAGCCCAUGGUGUUGGCUCUCAACGUGACCCGCAGUCUGAUCCCCUGUGAAGAGCCGGACAUCCCAGGCACACGUGUGCGCCACCUUCAGCAGGCAUUCGGGUGCUGGGCUGGUGGCUCAUCAGGCCUGGGCCCCACACUGACAAGCGCCAGAUACGCCACAAAUACCACUGUGUCAAAUGCUUUCAAGAUAUAUUUUUGGGGAAACUAUUUUUUAAACACUGUGGAAUACACUGGAAAUCUUCAGGGAAAAACACAUUUAAACACUUUUUUUUUUAAGGAAAGAAUUGGUAUAUUUAUUAUGUUCUGUUUUUCUAAAUAACCUGUGGACAAGGGAAGCCCCACUGAUUUACUCCCUCUCUUCCCCACUCCCUGUGAGGCUGGGCUGAGGCACGGAUCCCUGGGCCACAGAGCAAGUCUCCAAAUCAGACAGCUGCCUCAGCCCCUGGGAUGUGUGAUUUCAGCUCCUGUCACCUCAUGCAAGGGCGUGGAGACCAGUAGAGGUGUGGAGGCCAGGCAGAGAGAGGAGCCUGCUCUGCGGGGGGCCCAGCUCAUGGGCACUGCCCCUUCAGCUAGCCUGCCUCCGUCCCCUGAGUCCAACAGUGGGAGCCCUAGCUGGGAAGUUCUGAUCCCCAAAGCCACAGCAGGGGACUGAUGGCUAUAGCAGAAUGAGGUCGGGUCAGGACCCUCAAACACCAUCUGGGAACACCAAGCACCCUGAAUCGAGACUGCAGGAGCCCUGCGGGGUGAGACUGUGUCAGAGAUACACUGCUGGCCACAAGUGUCCCCUCUCAGUCCCACCUUUUCGGGCUGUCCCAUGUCUAUCUCAGGGGCCCGUUACCUCUCUGCAGCAGUCCCCCAUCCCAGCCACACCAGGGUCUGUCCGGCCAACCCUCUUCCCCAGGGAAAGGAGAAAAGAGAAAACAGGCUGGGCCCGGUGGCUCACUCCUGUAAUCCCAGCACUUUGGGAGGUUGAGGUGGGCGGAUCACCUGAGGUCAGGAGUUUGAGACCAGCCUGGCCAACGUGGUGAAACCCCAUCUCUACUAAAAAAAAUUACAAAAAUUAGCCGGGAGUGGUGGUGGGCACCUGUAAUCCCAGUUACUCGGGAGGCUGAGGCAAGAGAAUCUCUUGAGCUCAGGAGGCAGAGGUUGCAGUGAGCUGAGAUUGCGCCACUGCACUCCAGCCUGGGUGACAGAGGGAGACUCCGUCCCAAAAAAAAGAAAAGAGAAACAGCUGUCACCUCCCGCAGGACCCAAAUCCUCUCUCUGAGCACCGUCAUCCACCACAUGGCUGGGCCUGGCUCCCAGGACCAGUCCAGUCCUCUAGUGCCUUAUCUGAGGCUGCAGCCGCCAGUCUCCACCCCAAGGAGACAGCCCCUGCUCCUAGAUGCCCUUGGCCUCCGCAGUGCAGCCCCCAGGUGUCCUGACUGAAGCACAGGCCAUAGCCCCAUUUCCCCGGUGCCUGCAGGGCUAACCUCCACGGGAGCCCAGGAGCUCUGGCCGGCAGGUCCAUGGCACAGGGCAUCGGAAGACUGCAAAACUGCUGGACUUACCCUGGGCUGCAGUCCAUUGUCGGCCCCUGGGUUGAAUCAAGAUAGUACUUGCAGCUAGAUGGAUGCUUUUAGCCAGGGGACAUUGUGAGGGGAAGAUUCCUCCACCCAGUCUGGCCUGUGGUGUCUGUCUCCUCCCUGAGACCACAGCUUCUCCAGUAGCAGACUCAUGGGCGCCACCAAGUGGAAGCACCUGGAGCGGCCUCUGCCAUCCAGUGGGGAAGCCAGGCCCCGAGACGGAGGUGGGGGCAGCACGUGCCCUCCACAGCCACCGCUUUCCCGCCUCAGCAGCCCAGGCCUCCUGGCCCAGCCCUGCCUGGACAGUGCUCUCCCCUCACCCGGGAAGCUGGAAUCCUCCUGCCCGAGAGGAAGCAGACGGCACAGGGACACCCCUGCCACCUUGGGAUCUGCCUCCAAGCUGGUGCAGGGUAUCGAGAGUGGAUUCCAGAUGGAGGUCCUGGUCCCAGCACGCAGCAGUCCUGGUAGCUCUGCAGAGGAGACAGGAACCCGAGAAGUAGCUGAAGCAGAAGCCAGCCGCAGUCCCCUUGCCACAUAGAGGCGGGCUUCUCCCAGCCAUGGUGUCCCCUCUGCCUCCCCUCCCCCGACCCUCCUGCCUUCCGCGUGGAGGGUGGUGGUCCUGUAGUGUCAGCACCAGCACCAUGGGCUUGGACCCCCUCCCUGGACACAGGCAGGUGUCCUAGGGCUGGGGGUGCAGCCCGAGGGAAUGGAGACCACACUCAUGGCUCAGGUCUGCCGGGGCCGGCAGGGGGUUGGGGAAGAAGAGGGCUCAGGCCCAGCAGGGGUGGAAGCCCCUGCCACUGCCACUACCCGCUCCAGAGCUUUAAGGAAAAUGAAGUGAGACCCCUCCCCUUAGGCCUGGGGAGCCAUAGGGCUGGCUUCUCUGUGGGUGCGUGGACGUGGGGUUGGGAGCUGGGAAUCUAUUUUUUGUAUUAUGUUUUGAGCUACUGUAGUUUUGGCGUGGCACUAUUGUAAUGGAAAUAAAAUACUUGUACGGAG